GGACUUGGGCGGCCCCUCCGCAGGCGGACCGGGGGCAAAGGAGGUGGCAUGUCGGUCAGGCACAGCAGGGUCCUGUGUCCGCGCUGAGCCGCGCUCUCCCUGCUCCAGCAAGGACCAUGAGGGCGCUGGAGGGGCCAGGCCUGUCGCUGCUGUGCCUGGUGUUGGCGCUGCCUGCCCUGCUGCCGGUGCCGGCUGUACGCGGAGUGGCAGAAACACCCACCUACCCCUGGCGGGACGCAGAGACAGGGGAGCGGCUGGUGUGCGCCCAGUGCCCCCCAGGCACCUUUGUGCAGCGGCCGUGCCGCCGAGACAGCCCCACGACGUGUGGCCCGUGUCCACCGCGCCACUACACGCAGUUCUGGAACUACCUAGAGCGCUGCCGCUACUGCAACGUCCUCUGCGGGGAGCGUGAGGAGGAGGCACGGGCUUGCCACGCCACCCACAACCGUGCCUGCCGCUGCCGCACCGGCUUCUUCGCGCACGCUGGUUUCUGCUUGGAGCACGCAUCGUGUCCACCUGGUGCCGGCGUGAUUGCCCCGGGCACCCCCAGCCAGAACACGCAGUGCCAGCCGUGCCCCCCAGGCACCUUCUCAGCCAGCAGCUCCAGCUCAGAGCAGUGCCAGCCCCACCGCAACUGCACGGCCCUGGGCCUGGCCCUCAAUGUGCCAGGCUCUUCCUCCCAUGACACCCUGUGCACCAGCUGCACUGGCUUCCCCCUCAGCACCAGGGUACCAGGAGCUGAGGAGUGUGAGCGUGCCGUCAUCGACUUUGUGGCUUUCCAGGACAUCUCCAUCAAGAGGCUGCAGCGGCUGCUGCAGGCCCUCGAGGCCCCGGAGGGCUGGGGUCCGACACCAAGGGCGGGCCGCGCGGCCUUGCAGCUGAAGCUGCGUCGGCGGCUCACGGAGCUCCUGGGGGCGCAGGACGGGGCGCUGCUGGUGCGGCUGCUGCAGGCGCUGCGCGUGGCCAGGAUGCCCGGGCUGGAGCGGAGCGUCCGUGAGCGCUUCCUCCCUGUGCACUGAUCCUGGCCCCCUCUUAUUUAUUCUACAUCCUUGGCACCCCACUUGCACUGAAAGAGGCUUUUUUUUAAAUAGAAGAAAUGAGGUUUCUUAAAGCUUAUUUUUAUAAAGCUUUUUCAUAAAA